GAAGCCCGAACCGAAGGAGCGGGCAUGAGGCGCUGCCCGUGCCGUGGGAGCCUGAACGAGGCGGAGGCCGGGGCGCUGCCCGCGGCGGCCCGCAUGGGACUGGAGGCGCCGCGAGGAGGGCGGCGGCGGCAGCCGGGACAGCAGCGACCUGGGCCCGGCGCAGGGGCCCCGGCGGGGCGGCCGGAGGGGGGCGGGCCCUGGGCCCGGACAGAGGGGUCCAGCCUCCACAGCGAGCCUGAGAGGGCCGGCCUCGGGCCUGCGCCGGGGACAGAGAGUCCGCAGGCAGAAUUCUGGACAGACGGACAGACUGAGCCCGCGGCAGCUGGCCUUGGAGUAGAGACCGAGAGGCCCAAGCAAAAGACGGAGCCAGACAGGUCCAGCCUCCGGACGCAUCUAGAAUGGAGCUGGUCAGAGCUGGAGACGACUUGUCUUUGGACGGAGACCGGGACAGAUGGCCUUUGGACUGAUCCGCACAGGUCCGACCUCCAGUUUCAGCCCGAGGAGGCCAGCCCCUGGACACAGCCAGGGGUUCAUGGGCCCUGGACAGAGCUGGAAACGCAUGGGUCACAGACUCAGCCAGAGAGGGUCAAGUCCUGGGCUGAUAACCUCUGGACCCACCAGAACAGUUCCAGCCUCCAGACUCACCCAGAAGGAGCCUGUCCCUCAAAAGAGCCAAGUGCUGAUGGCUCCUGGAAAGAAUUGUAUACUGAUGGCUCCAGGACACAACAGGAUAUUGAAGGUCCCUGGACAGAGCCAUAUACUGAUGGCUCCCAGAAAAAACAGGAUACUGAAGCAGCCAGGAAACAGCCUGGCACUGGUGGUUUCCAAAUACAACAGGAUACUGAUGGCUCCUGGACACAACCUAGCACUGACGGUUCCCAGACAGCACCUGGGACAGACUGCCUCUUGGGAGAGCCUGAGGAUGGCCCAUUAGAGGAACCAGAGCCUGGAGAAUUGCUGACUCACCUGUACUCUCACCUGAAGUGUAGCCCCCUGUGCCCUGUGCCCCGCCUCAUCAUUACCCCUGAGACCCCUGAGCCUGAGGCCCAGCCAGUGGGACCCCCCUCCCGGGUUGAGGGGGGCAGCGGCGGCUUCUCCUCUGCCUCUUCUUUCGACGAGUCUGAGGAUGACGUGGUGGCCGGGGGCGGAGGUGCCAGCGAUCCCGAGGACAGGUCUGGGAGCAAACCCUGGAAGAAGCUGAAGACAGUUCUGAAGUAUUCACCCUUUGUGGUCUCCUUCCGAAAACACUACCCUUGGGUCCAGCUUUCUGGACAUGCUGGGAACUUCCAGGCAGGAGAGGAUGGUCGGAUUCUGAAACGUUUCUGUCAGUGUGAGCAGCGCAGCCUGGAGCAGCUGAUGAAAGACCCGCUGCGACCUUUCGUGCCUGCCUACUAUGGCAUGGUGCUGCAGGAUGGCCAGACCUUCAACCAGAUGGAAGACCUCCUGGCUGACUUUGAGGGCCCCUCCAUUAUGGACUGCAAGAUGGGCAGCAGGACCUAUCUGGAAGAGGAGCUAGUGAAGGCACGGGAACGUCCCCGUCCCCGGAAGGACAUGUAUGAGAAGAUGGUGGCUGUGGACCCUGGGGCCCCUACCCCUGAGGAGCAUGCCCAGGGUGCAGUCACCAAGCCCCGCUACAUGCAGUGGAGGGAAACCAUGAGCUCCACCUCUACCCUGGGCUUCCGGAUCGAGGGCAUCAAGAAGGCAGAUGGGACCUGUAACACCAACUUCAAGAAGACGCAGGCACUGGAGCAGGUGACAAAAGUGCUGGAGGACUUCGUGGAUGGAGACCACGUCAUCCUGCAAAAGUACGUGGCAUGCCUAGAAGAACUUCGUGAAGCUCUGGAGAUCUCCCCCUUCUUCAAGACCCACGAGGUGAUCUCCUCCAAACCCCCAGUGGAUGCCGGAAACUGUGGAUAGUACUGAACUAUAGACUGUGUUUUCUCGAUCUGAUAACCAAGAUGGCUCCUAGGUGACUAGUGGGUGGGUUGCGGAUACAGCAUAGACUUGCUGAACAAAGGGAUGAUUCGCAUCCCAGGUGGGACGAAGCGGGAUGGCACGAGAUUUCAUCACAGUAGUUAAACCAAUGUGCAACUUAAAACUUACACAUUGUUUGUUUCUGGAAUUUUCCACUUAAUAUUUUUGGAUCGCACUUGACUGAGAGUAACUAAAACCAAAGAAAAUGAAACCACGGACUGGGGAGACUAACUGUAUUACUCUCACUUUGUAUAUGAGGACGCAGAACCACAGAGAGGUUAAGACACCUGCCUAAGGCUGCACAGACAGGAGGUGGCACAGCCAGGAUAUGAAUCAGGCAGCCAGGCUCCAGGGUUCAUGCUGUCAAUCACCCUGCUCUGCUGCCUGUCAGGAAGGGACCUUGGCCAGUGCCUGCUCCUCCCUUAACCUCCCGUCUCUACCCCGGCAGGUGGUAGGCAGCUCCCUCCUCUUCGUGCACGACCACACCGGCCUGGCCAAGGUCUGGAUGAUAGACUUCGGCAAGACGGUGGCCUUGCCCGACCACCAGACGCUCAGCCACAGGCUGCCCUGGGCUGAGGGCAACCGUGAGGACGGCUACCUCUGGGGCCUGGACAACAUGAUCUGCCUCCUGCAGGGGCUGGCACAGAGCUGAGCUGCUCAGCCACCAUCAGGUUAAUUGGAUGGCGCCAGUCUGGCUGGAGGAGCCCUGAGAUGCCAUGGGAGGCCUGAGGUUGGCCACGGGGGAGCUGGCCUCCAGGGACGGGAGAGAUUGUGUCAUGUGCCACACGAGACCAACGUGGAAAAGUCUGAAGGGCCUUGGGAGACCAGGUAGCACCUGGCCCCAUCAUGAUGCAGGGGUUUUGGGGACCUGGAAGGAAGGUGAUGAGGCAGUGAGUCAGAAAAACCAGAACGGGGUCCCCGGAUCUGCCGGGAAGGCUUCUGAGGGGCUGCCCUGAGAGCAUUCAGUUCACAUGUCACAGGGUAUGGUGUGACAGGGUGCCUGUGGACACAUGAAUCACUUCUAACCUGCCUCCCUGUCAGCCUCCAGGCUGCCAGCUGGCUGAGGCCAGGGACUGGGUCAGGCUCAUCUGUGGCGCCUCAGAGGGUCAGCAUCAUUGGUGAACAGAUGCAGGCGCUGCUGGACCAUCUGGGGAGAGUGACAGUCCAUGUCUUCACCAGGGAGCCAUUUGAGUGCUGAGCGACAAGAGGCUCAGAGGGCAUGACCCCAUGGGACUGGAUGCGGCCUGAGGGCUGAUACCGCUGGGCGGUAUCCUGCCCUGCUGUGGCCCUGUGGGAUCCUCCGUGUUCCUCGGCGGACUCUGCUGACCUCCUGCAGACCCAAACCACAGCCACAUCCCAGCUUCUGUGCCAGCACUGUGACAGUACCUCGCUCCUCUGUGCACCAGAUCCGGCCUCAGGACUUACACCUCCUGCCUGACCCCCAGGCUUCUCUCUCCUUUCUCCCAGCAAACUGCAGUGGCAGAAAGGAGGUUCAGAGGCUGGGAAAGUGGGCCUCCCCUUGCAACUCAGAGCUGCUGCACUCAGGAGGGCCCCAUCCAAUCCCGGGCCCCUGCAGGGAAAAGCGCUGGGUGUGUGUCAGAGGCGCAGGGUGGGUGGGGCUGCCAGCCAGGACCCUGGCCUGCAGCCUGAUCCAAACCAAAGACUGUAGAACCCUGGGGUGUGGCUAACGGCCCCUCCAGCACCCAUAGCCAGGUCUUCCUGGCCCUUGAGGCUGGGCUGGCGGACAGGCACCUACCUCUUCCUUAAGCUGAAGCUCCCACACUGUCUUCCAGGGCUGAGGAGAUGCUCUCCUUUUCUACUGACCAUCUUGAUACUUAUUUAUACGAGAGGCAGUUGCUGGACGGGGUAGUACUGGGAAGCAGGAGGCAGAAUGGCUCUGCUGAGCCUCCUACCCAUGACAACACCCCAAUAAACAGAACAUUCAGAGCCAA